GUAUUGCGUUACAGAUUUAACAGCUGUGGUUUCAAGAUGUCUGGCCGCGGUAAGGGCGGAAAGGGUCUAGGUAAGGGUGGCGCCAAGCGUCACCGUAAGGUAUUGCGUGACAAUAUCCAAGGAAUCACCAAGCCCGCUAUCCGCCGCCUGGCUCGCCGCGGCGGCGUCAAGCGUAUUUCUGGCCUCAUUUAUGAGGAAACUCGCGGAGUGCUGAAAGUUUUCCUGGAAAAUGUAAUCCGCGAUGCUGUCACCUACACGGAACACGCCAAACGCAAGACAGUCACAGCCAUGGACGUGGUGUACGCGCUCAAGCGCCAGGGACGCACUCUUUAUGGCUUCGGCGGCUGAGCUUACCUCUACAGUACACUACCGCAAAACCAACGGCCCUUUUCAGGGCCACCUA